ACGCGCGGGGCGGGUGCUGCUUGCUGCAGGCUCUGGGGAGUCGCCAUGGUGAGUGCUGAGGGGGCAGUGGCACCUGGGUCGACCCUCCUUGUAGCCCCUGCUCUCUCCCACCGCCCCGCACUCCAGCGAGUGGAGAAGGGGCCCCACAGACCGUUCGGGAUUAAGACCAGCCCGAUUUGGCCUGCGGGAUAGGGGACAGCAGGAGGAAGGCCGCGGGCAGGCUGAUCCGGGCCGGGGUGGGCGGCGGCUCUUGGCUGCGGCCGUUGCUGAGAGACGGGGCGGCCUCUCUGUGGGGUUGACUUGGCAUGUAGGCUUUGGGGUCCAUGAAGGCCUGCGGCCUCCUUUAAGUGGAAUCGGUCACCUGCCUACCACGAGGGGACCGGUAGUCCUAGGUCUGAGCGUCUGGCCCCCGGGGCGCGUGGAGGCCCUGAGACUCGGAGGUGGCGCCGGGACCCGCCCAGAUGUUGCGUUUCUACCUUUGUGCCUAGUUGUGCUCGGCCGUCCCCACGCCCUCCUGGAGGGGUCGCAGUGAUUCCUUGGCCUUUCUUGGCCUCAUACCCGCCUUCGGCUGCAGUGUUUGUCAGCGAGUUCUGGGGACCUGCUUACAUGAAUUUCCUGGAAGGACUCAGGCUGUCUUCUAAUCCUGACGGUCGCAAAGGAGACUGAUUGUUUACUUUAGCAUUUGUGCAUUGGGCGCACCUUGCCUCUUUUGUCUCGCCAUUGAUAAAAUCCAAGUAUUUGACUUGCUGGAAGCAGUACUUCUCCUUAGGGCCCGUCUAUGACGGCAGCAAAUCGUGGUGUGGCUGUUGGCCGGUAAACUUGAACUUCCUCAAAAUGUGAAUCUUUGUGUCUGGUUCCCACAAAGCCUACAACACAGCAGUCCCCUCAGGAUGAGCAGGAAAAGCUCUUGGAUGAAGCCAUACAGGCUGUGAAGGUCCAGUCAUUCCAAAUGAAGAGAUGCCUGGACAAAAACAAGCUUAUGGAUGCUCUAAAACAUGCUUCUAAUAUGCUUGGUGAACUCCGGACUUCUAUGUUAUCACCAAAGAGUUACUAUGAACUUUAUAUGGCCAUUUCUGAUGAACUGCACUACUUGGAGGUCUACCUGACAGAUGAGUUUGCUAAAGGAAGGAAAGUGGCAGAUCUCUACGAACUUGUACAGUAUGCUGGAAACAUUAUCCCAAGGCUUUACCUUUUGAUCACAGUUGGAGUUGUAUAUGUCAAGUCAUUUCCUCAGUCCAGGAAGGAUAUUUUGAAAGAUUUGGUAGAAAUGUGCCGUGGUGUGCAACAUCCCUUGAGGGGUCUGUUUCUUCGAAAUUACCUUCUUCAGUGUACCAGAAAUAUCUUACCUGAUGAAGGAGAGCCAACAGAUGAAGAAACAACUGGUGACAUCAGUGAUUCCAUGGAUUUUGUACUGCUCAACUUUGCAGAAAUGAACAAGCUCUGGGUGCGAAUGCAGCAUCAGGGACAUAGCCGAGAUAGAGAAAAAAGAGAACGAGAAAGACAAGAACUGAGAAUUUUAGUGGGAACAAAUUUGGUGCGCCUCAGUCAGUUGGAAGGUGUAAAUGUGGAACGUUACAAACAGAUUGUUUUGACUGGCAUAUUGGAGCAAGUUGUAAACUGUAGGGAUGCUUUGGCUCAAGAAUAUCUCAUGGAGUGUAUUAUUCAGGUUUUCCCUGAUGAAUUUCACCUCCAGACUUUGAAUCCUUUUCUUCGGGCCUGUGCUGAGUUACACCAGAAUGUAAAUGUGAAGAACAUAAUCAUUGCUUUAAUUGAUAGAUUAGCUUUAUUUGCUCACCGUGAAGAUGGACCUGGAAUCCCAGCGGAUAUUAAACUUUUUGAUAUAUUUUCACAGCAGGUGGCUACAGUGAUACAGUCUAGACAAGACAUGCCUUCAGAGGAUGUUGUAUCUUUACAAGUCUCUCUGAUUAAUCUUGCCAUGAAAUGUUACCCUGAUCGUGUGGACUAUGUUGAUAAAGUUCUAGAAACAACAGUGGAGAUAUUCAAUAAGCUCAACCUUGAACAUAUUGCUACCAGUAGUGCAGUUUCAAAGGAACUCACCAGACUUUUGAAAAUACCAGUUGACACUUACAACAAUAUUUUAACAGUCUUGAAAUUAAAACAUUUUCACCCACUCUUUGAGUACUUUGACUACGAGUCCAGAAAGAGCAUGAGUUGUUAUGUGCUUAGUAAUGUUCUGGAUUAUAACACAGAAAUUGUCUCUCAAGACCAGGUGGAUUCCAUAAUGAAUUUGGUAUCCACGUUGAUUCAAGAUCAGCCAGAUCAACCUGUAGAAGACCCUGAUCCAGAAGAUUUUGCUGAUGAGCAGAGCCUUGUGGGCCGCUUCAUUCAUCUGCUGCGCUCUGAGGACCCUGACCAGCAGUACUUGAUUUUGAACACAGCACGAAAACAUUUUGGAGCUGGUGGAAAUCAGCGGAUUCGCUUCACACUGCCACCUUUGGUAUUUGCAGCUUACCAGCUGGCUUUUCGAUAUAAAGAGAAUUCUAAAGUGGAUGACAAAUGGGAAAAGAAAUGCCAGAAGAUUUUUUCAUUUGCCCACCAGACUAUCAGUGCUUUGAUCAAAGCAGAGCUGGCAGAAUUGCCCUUAAGACUUUUUCUUCAAGGAGCACUAGCUGCUGGGGAAAUUGGUUUUGAAAAUCAUGAGACAGUCGCAUAUGAAUUCAUGUCCCAGGCAUUUUCUCUGUAUGAAGAUGAAAUCAGCGAUUCCAAAGCACAGCUAGCUGCCAUCACCUUGAUCAUUGGCACUUUUGAAAGGAUGAAGUGCUUCAGUGAAGAGAAUCACGAACCUCUGAGGACUCAGUGUGCCCUUGCUGCAUCCAAACUUCUAAAGAAACCUGAUCAGGGCCGAGCUGUGAGCACCUGUGCACAUCUCUUCUGGUCUGGCAGAAACACGGACAAAAAUGGGGAGGAGCUUCACGGAGGCAAGAGGGUAAUGGAGUGCCUAAAAAAAGCUCUAAAAAUAGCAAAUCAGUGCAUGGACCCCUCUCUACAAGUGCAGCUUUUUAUAGAAAUUCUGAACAGAUAUAUCUAUUUUUAUGAAAAGGAAAAUGAUGCGGUAACAAUUCAGGUUUUAAACCAGCUUAUCCAAAAGAUUCGAGAAGACCUCCCGAAUCUUGAAUCCAGUGAAGAAACAGAGCAGAUUAACAAACAUUUUCAUAACACACUGGAGCAUUUGCGCUUGCGGCGGGAAUCACCAGAAUCCGAGGGGCCAAUUUAUGAAGGUCUCAUCCUUUAAAAAGGAAAUAGCUCACCAUACUCCUUUCCAUGUACAUCCAGUGAGGGUUUUAUUACGCUAGGUUUCCCUUCCAUAGAUUGUGCCUUUCAGAAAUGCUGAGGUAGGUUUCCCAUUUCUUACCUGUGAUGUGUUUUACCCAGCACCUCCGGACACUCACCUUCAGGACCUUAAUAAAAUUAUUCACUUGGUAAGUGUUCAAGUCUUUCUGAUCACCCCAAGUAGCAUGACUGAUCUGCAAUUUAAAAUUCCUGUGAUCUGUAAAAAAAAAAAAAAAAAAAAACACAAAACCCACAAGCACUUAUCUUGGCUACUAAUGAAGCUCUCCUUUUUUUUGUUUGUUUGUUUGCUUCAUUGUUGAUUGUGUAUUUUCUUCAUUCCUGGGGAGUACUAACCCAAAAGCGUCUGUCUCUUGUUUUCUAGUCCAGUUUGAGAUUAAUUUAGAAGAAAGGAAUACUGUAUGUGAAAUUCAUCUUGGGCUUUCCCCUAAAUUGCAAGAUAAGGCCAUGUGUAAGAUUUUCCCUAAAACUAGAAUAUAUUAAUGCAUGUUUGAGAAUUUUAAAGCACCAUGGUCAAAACCAGAAGCUAUAUUUUGCAUAUUUGGACUCAGCCAUCCAUUAAGAACCCAUGUUGUCCUCUGGACAUAUUUAUCAAUAUAAUUGGGUUUUAAAUAGUAUAAAAGAAAACUUGUGAUCUAUAUAAUUUAUGUAUCACCUUCAUUGUAAAUUUAGCAGGAAAUGCAUCACAAUUAUGAUUUUUUUUUUUGCACCAGUGAAACAAUAAAGAUGCUAUUAACAAUUUUGGAGCUUUUUUUCCCCUUUCAUACUAUCUUUAAUUGAUAAAAAGUACUAGUAGUAUGGCUAUAGAGUUUAAUAGUCAUUCUCAUAUAUUCACAGAGCUCACUUAACUCUAGUUUUAAGCACUUGUUGAACAAGGCAGCAUCUACUCUUUUAGUCAUUUAUACCCCUUUUCUUUCCUCAACUUUACCCUGCUUUUCCCAAGGCAUGAUGAAUUCACAUAAACCCCCCAAAGGCUCACCACCGAUACUAGUUACCUACUAUAUAAUAAACCAUCCCAAAACUUACUGUCUUAAAACAGCAAACAUUUAUCUCACAGGUCUCUGGAUCAGGAAUUUGGGAGCAGCUUAGCUGGUGGUUCUGGCAAAGAGUGUGGUGUAAGGUUGCAAACAAGAUACUGGUUGGGGCUGCAGUCAUCUGAUGCUUUGACUGGGGCUGACUUUUCUGCUCACUGACCUGGCUGUUAGGCAGAGGCCCCAGUUCCUCUUCUUGAGGGCAGAGGCCCCAGUUCCUCUCCUUGAGGGCAGAGGCCUAAGUUCCUUUCCUUGAGGGCAGAGGCCCCAGUUCCUCUCCUUGACGGCCCUUCCAUAGAGUGUCCUCACAGCAUGGUGGCUGGCUUUCCCCUGAGUAUGAAAGCAAGAAGGAAACCACAGUGCCUUUCAGUGGCCUCCCUGUGGAAGUGACAUGCUCAUUUUUGCCUUAUUCUGUAAGUGGGGAGUCACUAAGUCUAGCCUAUAUUCAAGGGUAAGGAGAAUUAAGCUCCACCUCUUAAAGGGAAAAUUUAUAGACAUUUUCAAAUGACUACAUCACUUAACCCCUCACCAUCUGCCCUCCCAUUGCUAGCACUUGAUGACUAGCCCUUGCUGGGCUUUACAUGAACAGAUGUUUCCCAAAGUUAUAAAAUUAGUACCACUAAAAUGUAUCAAAUGUUAAGCCAUUCUGUGGUAUGUCAUAGUCCAGCAAACCCUUUCUGUUCUUUGUAGGUGUUAGUUUACCCCGUAUAAACCUGAUUAUGGCUUGACAUGUCCAUAUUAUUUACAUGUUUUGUGAAAUACAACUGGAAUAGUAGAAAAGACAUGAGUCAAGAACACUUGAGUUGGAGAGCUUGGUUUGCAAGUAAGGUAAUGUCAGUACAGUGUGUAAAUUAUCUCUUAUUUUCUGGGUUGAGGUAAACCCAAUUUUAAAAAUAAUAAACCAACAAAAGUAAAUAAAAGUGAAACAAAAGCACUGCUAGUAUCCUUAACUUACAGAUUUUUUUUGUUGAACAAAAACUGGGUACCAGAUAUAGUUAGGCACUGAAUCUAAAGGUGAAGAAGAUCAUAGCCUCUAGCUUCAAGAACGUUAGUCUGCUGUGAAGACAGACCUGUAGUUACAGAAGAUGGUAAGGGUUUGUGCAGGAGAGCAGUGAAGAAGAGCUUUGAGGGAUUGGGGAUGGGGAAGUUCUGCAGAGGGUUGUAUGAAUUCUCAUGGAACAUCAAGUCCAAUAGUUUAUUUAGCCUUCUGAGGCCAGUGCUUUGGCCUGCAGUCCCAGGCUCCUCAGACCCAUGGGCUGAAGCAAGUUAUACUCUUGGCUGCCUGUAGUGAAAUAGAUAUUUAGAAAUUGACUUAGCAUUUAAAACCCUUUAUAGCAAUUUGACAGAGUAAUUUUAUGUCUAUUGGAUGUAAUAAAUAUUUGGCUUUGUGCUUUGUGUGUCUGCUAUUCCCUGUUCUCCUUUUUUAGUAAUUUUUAUUGUGUCUUACAAAAAAGUACCUGUCCUUAAUUGGGGUGUGGUGGGGAAUCCCUCACAGGUGGAUGGAAACGCUGAACCAGGGCAGGCUUGGUGCUGAAUGGCAUUAAAUUCCAAGACUAGGGGAUAGUUUGGGGGGACACAUCUAGGAAGAUGCUGUGACUGGAUGAGAGAUGCCUGCCGUGUUAGACUUUCCUACCCUCCCUUUCCUGCCUCUACCCAGGAAACCAGUGAUUCUUAGAGUCCAGAUGAUCCCUUCUUUGCCUAGAAAUUCAUGUUUCUGACUCAUCCUCAAGCCUGAAAUUGGUGGUCAUCAGGUUAAUGAACUGCAAAAACAGCCCCUGCUGAUAGACACUGCUCAAAGAGAGAGGCGUUUGAGUUGAUCAGGCACCAGAGCACCUAGAAGGAGAAUGAUGAGCACUUGUGUACAGUUCGUGUGCAGCUCUCAAAGGCAUUGAGAAAUGUGACAGACCUCAAGGAAUAAAUGCACCACCACAGGCACUGAGGGGAUUUAAACACAAAGUCUAGGUUCCAGAGGGGUCUUCUGUUAACAUUUGCUCUCUCAUUCAGAGACCUCAAGGUAAUAAGCUCAAGCAGAAAGGAUUUCCCAACAGAAUUGUCUUUGACAAUGGGAAUUCCAGACUGCAUAUUGUAAAUGAAAGGUAGAGAAAUCUGUGCAGGAGACCUUCCUGUUUGCUGGGGUUUGUCCUAUGGGGAUGCUGUAGGCAUGGACAACAGACACUGAUUCAGGUGCCAGUAUCUACACAUUUACCAUACACUUGAAUUCCCAAGAGUAGUGACUUGCCUUAGGUUUGAUUAAAGACAAAUGUUUCCUGGCUUGUGGUCUUGUAUUGCUGAUUACUCCAGUAGGGCACCCUGCAUUGUCCAACAAAAUGGUCCAUGCUUCCAAAAUCUCUGGAGAGGGACUGUAUAUUUUAUUUUUUUGAGACGGAGUCUUGCUCUGUCACCCAAGCAGGAGUGCAGUGGUGCGAUCUUGGCUCACUGCAACCUCCGCCUCCCCAGUUCAAGCAAUUCUCCUGCCUCAGCCUCCCGAGUAGCUGGGAUUACAGGCGUGCACCACCAUGCCUGGCUAAUUUUUGUAUUUUUAGUACAGAUGGGGGUUUCACCAUGUUGGCCAGGCUGGUCACGAACUUCUGACCUUGUGAUCCACCUGGCUCAGCCUCCCAAAGUGCUGGAAUUACAGGCAUGAGCCACCUUGCCCAGCCAGAUUGUAUAUUGUACCACUCAUUGCUGUGUUCAGGCUUGCAUCAGUAGUGUCUUCAAAUAAGUAAAAUCUUAGGCUGUGACUUAAAUCCAUUUUCACUUAGAGAAAUAGAAACACAAGGAAACCUUUGGACGCUUCAUAACUGCUGGGAAAGGGGUAUUAUCAAUUGUGUUUGAGAGUCAAACUAUAAAUUACUUCCCAAGGUUAGUUCUACCUAUGCCCAGGAAUGAACAAGGACAGCUUAAAGGUUAGAAGCAAGAUGGAGUCAUUUGGGUCUGAUCUCUUUCACUGUCAUAAUUUCCUCAGUUACAAUUUUUGUAAAGGUGGUUUCAAAUGCUUUGCUGACCUCCCAUAAACAAGGAUGUGCCAAUUGUAACUUCAGUUCUGCAAUUCAAGUCUGCUCCCAAAACUAAAGUCCAUUGAAUUGCAUACUGAUUGAUAAUGUUCAUUACGAGUUUAUCUUCCCAUGUGCAGAGCAAAGACAAGAGGAGAUCAGCCAUUCCUCCACCUACCCAGAGACGUUGCAUUGGAAAGGAGCCGUAUCUUCUAGUAUGGUUUUGCAAAUGUAAAAUGUAAAAUCUAUGCACGCUCACA